AGCAUCAGCACUGACACCAGGCUGGGAACCUCGCAGCCGGGGCUGAGGCAGCCAGCAGGGCAGGUCUUGAAACUCCUGAAACCUCAGCUGGAGGUCUGUCAGUGAGGACCACACCUCGCCCUCCAUCCCUGCGACUGCCUGUACUGGCCAAAACCAGGAACACACCAAGGCUACCAACUUCUGGACUCGAAGCACUGGACAGAAUCCAGCCCAAGGAGGCCCCCAACCAGAUACCCAACUCCAAGGCACCUCCCACCUGCCCAGGGCGCAAAUCGUCAACGGUCCCAGCUACAAUGCAGGCCGCUGGGCACCCAGAGCCCCUUGACAGCAGGGGCUCCUUCUCCCUCCCCACGAUGGGUGCCAACGUCUCUCAGGACAAUGGCACUGGCCACAAUGCCACCUUCUCCGAGCCACUGCCGUUCCUCUAUGUGCUCCUGCCCGCCGUGUACUCCGGGAUCUGUGCUGUGGGGCUGACUGGCAACACGGCCGUCAUCCUUGUAAUCCUAAGGGCGCCCAAGAUGAAGACGGUGACCAACGUGUUCAUCCUGAACCUGGCCGUCGCCGACGGGCUCUUCACGCUGGUACUGCCCGUCAACAUCGCGGAGCACCUGCUGCAGUACUGGCCCUUCGGGGAGCUGCUCUGCAAGCUGGUGCUGGCCGUCGACCACUACAACAUCUUCUCCAGCAUCUACUUCCUAGCCGUGAUGAGCGUGGACCGAUACCUGGUGGUGCUGGCCACCGUGAGGUCCCGCCACAUGCCCUGGCGCACCUACCGGGGGGCGAAGGUCGCCAGCCUGUGUGUCUGGCUGGGCGUCACGGUCCUGGUUCUGCCCUUCUUCUCUUUCGCUGGCGUCUACAGCAACGAGCUGCAGGUCCCAAGCUGUGGGCUGAGCUUCCCGUGGCCCGAGCAGGUCUGGUUCAAGGCCAGCCGUGUCUACACGUUGGUCCUGGGCUUCGUGCUGCCCGUGUGCACCAUCUGUGUGCUCUACACAGACCUCCUGCGCAGGCUGCGGGCCGUGCGGCUCCGCUCUGGAGCCAAGGCUCUAGGCAAGGCCAGGCGGAAGGUGACCGUCCUGGUCCUCGUCGUGCUGGCCGUGUGCCUCCUCUGCUGGACGCCCUUCCACCUGGCCUCUGUCGUGGCCCUGACCACGGACCUGCCCCAGACCCCACUGGUCAUCAGUAUGUCCUACGUCAUCACCAGCCUCAGCUACGCCAACUCGUGCCUGAACCCCUUCCUCUACGCCUUUCUAGAUGACAACUUCCGGAAGAACUUCCGCAGCAUAUUGCGGUGCUGAAGGGCCUGGGCACCAUCACCCCCAUCAUCAUGCCCAUCAUCACCCCCCAUCAUCAUCACGCCCAUCAUCAUCAUGCCCACACCCCCAUCAGGCCCACCCCCCCCCACCCCCACCACCACCCCCACCAUCACCCCCACCACCACCCCCAUCAUCACGCCCAUCAUCAUGCCCACCCCCAUCACAUCCACCAUCACGCCCACCCCCAUCACCCCCACCCCCACCAUCACGCCCACCAUCACCCCCACCCCCACCCCCACCCCCAUCAUCACGCCCACCCCCCCCACCACCCCCACCAUCACCCCCAUCAUCACGCCCACCCCCACCCAGUUCCGGCUGUCUCUUUCAGGGGACGCCCGGCCUGUUCACAUCCCAGUGCUGUCCUCUCCACGCAAGGAGACACAGACCCUCACACGCUGGCCACCAGACCUACAGACAGCCGUGGGCAUAUACCUCCCAUGUCUCUGCUUCCUGGACAGCCCCUGGGUGGACAGCAGCAGGGAUCCAGGUCCUGGCAGAGGCCCCCACACAGCAAGCAUCCCGGGCCCACUUACCCACGAGAGACAGACAGAUGGACAAGCCCCUUGGAAGGCUCUGGGACUCAGGAUCCCUAAUGACAGUGGUCGGGAGGGGAGGGAACCUGAACUGUGAUCUUGACCUGGGCCACGUUACAUAGUCUCUCCCCAAGAUGGGGCCGGGGGGUGGUAAGUGCGGGCACCUCAGGCAGCAGCGAUGCUGUGUUGCUGCAAAGGCGGACACCUGCACCGCAUGAGACCCAGAAAUCCACUCUCGUGGCCUGAAGCCCAAGUGGAGUUCCAGCAGGAGGCCCAGCCCCGCCGUGCCCAUGUGCCAUGGCCUGUGCUGCUGUGUUCCCCCUGCUGUGGCCGACGGUCCUUGCCAUGGCCUGUACCCGCCCUGCUGUGUCCGACAGUCCUCUCCAUGGCCUGUGCUCCCCUGUGCCCCCCUGCUGUGUCCGACGGUCCUCUCCAUGGCCUGUGCUCCCCUGUACCCCCCUGCUGUGGCCGACAGUCCUCACCAUGGCCUGUGCUCCCCUGUGCCCCCCUGCUGUGGCCGACAGUCCUCACCAUGGCCUGUGCUCCCCUAUACUCCCCUGCUGUGGCCGACGGUCCUCUCCAUGGCCUGUGCUCCCCUGUACCCCCCUGCUGUGUCUGACGGUCCUCUCCAUGGCCUGUGCUCCCCUAUACUCCCCUGCUGUGGCCGACGGUCCUCUCCAUGGCCUGUGCUCCCCUGCUGUGGCCGACAGUCCUCACCAUGGCCUGUGCUCCCCUGUGCCCCCCUGCUGUGUCUGACGGUCCUCUCCAUGGCCUGUGCUCCCCUGUACCCCCCUGCUGUGGCCGACGGUCCUCGCCAUGGCCUGUACACCCCUGCUGUGGCCGAUGCUCCUCUCAUACUUUACUAGAGGCUACAGGGCCCUUUUGCCAGGACCUCUGGGCCACCACAGCCUAGGGACCAUCCAUCACUUGGACAGGCUGGCACCUGGAACUCUCUCUCCCGGGGUGUGGCCAGGGGCUUGUAAUCAGCCAGCAGGAGCUGCAUGCUGAAACUCUGGUGGGGGCAGGGUGAGGGGUGGUAAUGAAAUGCAGGCAGUUCAGAGACCGCUGACUGUCAGGUGGGAGGGGCCAGGGGUUGGUCCCAGGUGUGCUGUGGCCAGGCCCCGACUCUUGGCCCCAUGGCUCUCAGCUGGUUCCAUGCCUGGCAUUCCAGCCUGGCAGUGAGGUGUGAGUGUUCUGGGUUGGUUUCAGUCCUCAUGACCCAGAGCUCUGAUCAAUCUGUCCAGCCGGCACACAGGACCCACCAUUCACCGCCCCACGAGGUGUCCCAGGGUGUAUGCCCACCUCCACCCAUCCACCAAAUACUCCAGCGUUCCAGCCCACUCGGCUCAGGCCUGCAGCAGUGCCCCUCCUCCGUGCUAGCCAGCCAAACACGCCACGGCCAUCUCCAUCCACUUAUCCUCCCUGACAACAUUGUAUUAGAUAUCUGUUGCUGAAUAACAAAUUUCUCCAAAACUUA